AUGGAUCUUAAAAAUGGAUCUCUAGUGACCGAGUUUAUUUUACUAGGAUUUUUUGGACGAUGGGAACUUCAAAUUUUCUUCUUUGUGACAUUUUCCCUGAUCUACGGUGCUACUGUGAUGGGAAACAUUCUCAUUAUGGUCACAGUGACAUGUAGGUCAACCCUUCAUUCUCCCUUGUACUUUCUCCUUGGAAAUCUCUCUUUUUUGGACAUGUGUCUCUCCACUGCCACAACACCCAAGAUGAUCAUAGAUUUGCUCACUGACCACAAGACCAUCUCUGUGUGGGGCUGCGUGACCCAGAUGUUCUUCAUGCACUUCUUUGGGGGUGCUGAGAUGACUCUUCUGAUAAUCAUGGCCUUUGACAGGUAUGUAGCCAUAUGUAAACCCCUGCACUAUAGGACAAUCAUGAGCCACAAGCUGCUAAAGGGGUUUGCGAUACUUUCAUGGAUAAUUGGUUUUUUACACUCCAUAAGCCAGAUAGUUUUAACAAUGAACUUGCCUUUCUGUGGCCACAAUGUCAUAAACAACAUAUUUUGUGAUCUUCCCCUUGUGAUCAAGCUUGCUUGCAUUGAAACAUACACCCUGGAAUUAUUUGUCAUUGCUGACAGCGGGCUGCUCUCUUUCACCUGUUUCAUCCUCUUGCUUGUUUCUUACAUUGUCAUCCUGGUCAGUGUACCAAAAAAAUCAUCACAUGGGCUCUCCAAGGCGCUGUCCACAUUGUCUGCCCACAUCAUUGUGGUCACUCUGUUCUUUGGACCUUGUAUUUUUAUCUAUGUUUGGCCAUUCAGUAGUUUGGCAAGCAAUAAAACUCUUGCCGUAUUUUAUACAGUUAUCACACCCUUACUGAAUCCGAGUAUUUAUACCCUGAGAAAUAAGAAAAUGCAAGAGGCCAUAAGAAAAUUACGGUUCCAAUAUGUUAGUUCUGCACAGAAUUUCUAG